AGCUCCCAUGCAGCCCACAGCCCUAAAGGCCGGUUUCACUCCCACCAUGCCCCACCAACAGCAAUGAGUUUACUUCCAGGAAGCUGGUGAGCAGGGCUGAGAACUUGCUCCAGGCUACAAGCCUCCCAGCUGAGAAAACGAGCGAACUCACAGUUCCUCGACUGUCCCAUGGAGCCUGCAGUGGCAAUCCGCCUCCUUCAAAGGGUCUGUGGACUUUCUCGGCUUUCCUGAUCUCAGAAACACAGCUUUUACAAAGGAUAAAUGAAGAGAAAUUCACCAGAGAUACAUUGUAAUGAAUCUGUAAAUCACCAAAGCUAAAGAUAUUAUUUCACAAGUGGAAUGACAGCUGACUUCUCAACAACAACGAAAGCAAGGAGACAGUUGAAAGACAUCUUGAAAAUGGAAUUAGCAGUUCACAAAGCACAUUCGCAUAUAAGGGCUUGUUUUGAAUUGAUCUUGGCAGCAAUUCUAUGAGACAAGUAAAAGCACAAGAGGAAUAGGAACUGCACCUCUUCCUUCAGUUUCAGCUUGAAUAAUAUCAGGAAGAUUCGUAUCGGUCUGAGUUGGGUCACGUACCCGACGUGCUAUAGCUGAGGAUGGGCUGACUUGUAUGAAGAAGGAGGUGGAGGAGGAGGAGAAGGUGAAGACAAUGCUGACUCAAAGGGGGGAUUAUAAAACUAAUCAUCAAAGCCAAGAAGGCAAGAGCAAGCAUGUACCGCUGAAAACACAAGAUAACUGCAUAAGUAAUGACUUUCAGUGCAGAUUCAUAGCUAACCCAUAAACUGCUGGGGCAAAAAUCAUCUUGGAAGGCUCUGAACCUCAGAAAGGAUUCACAAGACGAUCUGCCGACCCUCUGGGAGAAAAUCCAGCAAGAUGCAAGCCUUCAGAAUCUGGGAUGUUAACCAGAAGACCUUCUAUCUGAGGAACAACCAACUAGUUGCUGGAUACUUGCAAGGACCAAAUGUCAAUUUAGAAGAAAAGAUAGAUGUGGUACCCAUUGAGCCUCAUGCUCUGUUCUUGGGAAUCCAUGGAGGGAAGAUGUGCCUGUCCUGUGUCAAGUCUGGUGAUGAGACCAGACUCCAGCUGGAGGCAGUUAACAUCACUGACCUGAGCGAGAACAGAAAGCAGGACAAGCGCUUCGCCUUCAUCCGCUCAGACAGUGGCCCCACCACCAGUUUUGAGUCUGCCGCCUGCCCCGGUUGGUUCCUCUGCACAGCGAUGGAAGCUGACCAGCCCGUCAGCCUCACCAAUAUGCCUGACGAAGGCGUCAUGGUCACCAAAUUCUACUUCCAGGAGGACGAGUAGUACUGCCCAGGCCUGCCUGUUCCCAUUCUUGCAUGGCAAGGACUGCAGGGACUGCCAGUCCCCCUGCCCCAGGGCUCCCGGCUAUGGGGGCACUGAGGACCAGCCAUUGAGGGGUGGACCCUCAGAAGGCGUCACAACAACCUGGUCACAGGACUCUGCCUCCUCUUCAACUGACCAGCCUCCAUGCUGCCUCCAGAAUGGUCUUUCUAAUGUGUGAAUCAGAGCACAGCAGCCCCUGCACAAAGCCCUUCCAUGUCGCCUCUGCAUUCAGGAUCAAACCCCGACCACCUGCCCAACCUGCUCUCCUCUUGCCACUGCCUCUUCCUCCCUCAUUCCACCUUCCCAUGCCCUGGAUCCAUCAGGCCACUUGAUGACCCCCAACCAAGUGGCUCCCACACCCUGUUUUACAAAAAAGAAAAGACCAGUCCAUGAGGGAGGUUUUUAAGGGUUUGUGGAAAAUGAAAAUUAGGAUUUCAUGAUUUUUUUUUUUCAGUCCCCGUGAAGGAGAGCCCUUCAUUUGGAGAUUAUGUUCUUUCGGGGAGAGGCUGAGGACUUAAAAUAUUCCUGCAUUUGUGAAAUGAUGGUGAAAGUAAGUGGUAGCUUUUCCCUUCUUUUUCUUCUUUUUUUGUGAUGUCCCAACUUGUAAAAAUUAAAAGUUAUGGUACUAUGUUAGCCCCAUAAUUUUUUUUUUCCUUUUAAAACACUUCCAUAAUCUGGACUCCUCUGUCCAGGCACUGCUGCCCAGCCUCCAAGCUCCAUCUCCACUCCAGAUUUUUUACAGCUGCCUGCAGUACUUUACCUCCUAUCAGAAGUUUCUCAGCUCCCAAGGCUCUGAGCAAAUGUGGCUCCUGGGGGUUCUUUCUUCCUCUGCUGAAGGAAUAAAUUGCUCCUUGACAUUGUAGAGCUUCUGGCACUUGGAGACUUGUAUGAAAGAUGGCUGUGCCUCUGCCUGUCUCCCCCACCGGGCUGGGAGCUCUGCAGAGCAGGAAACAUGACUCGUAUAUGUCUCAGGUCCCUGCAGGGCCAAGCACCUAGCCUCGCUCUUGGCAGGUACUCAGCGAAUGAAUGCUGUAUAUGUUGGGUGCAAAGUUCCCUACUUCCUGUGACUUCAGCUCUGUUUUACAAUAAAAUCUUGAAAAUGCC